AAGAGAGGAGGAAGGAGGAAGGAGCUGAGGAGGGAUGAGAGAGGCGGCCAGGGCCCCGGGCCGUAGCAGCGCGGGGCUGGGGGACCAGGGGGGCUGAGACACCCCAACUGCCCCCUUCCCCUUUCCCUCUCCCCCUCUAUCCUUUCCUUCCACCCUCCCGCUUGAGGAGGGGGAUUUAUUCAAAUUUUAUUUAAAUCCCUAUCUCCCGAGGGUCGCGCGCUUGGGGGAGGGGGAGAGGUCGGGGGUGCGCGCGGGCUGGGGGGGGCGGGGCCGGAGCAGCUUCCUUCACCUCCCCCUCCGCUCGCCUCGCAGCCGUAGGGCAGGGGGUCGCAGUCCAGGGGCGGGCCCAGGGGAGGGGGGCAGGUUACAGCGACCCCCCCCUCCCCGGGAACCGGCGGUGGGCGGGCUUGAACCCCGGAAACGGUGGGGGGGGCCCAGGCCUGGCACUGGACCCCUGGGCAGUGGGGUCCGGGAAGGGGCCAGUUAAAGGGCCAGGGGCGCUGGGGAGAGGCGGGGCGGGGUGGGGGGAGGGGAGCUGGGACUCGGACCCGGGACUGAGUGGGCCCCGGGCAGAAGCUGAGCACCCUGCGCCCAAGGAGCCCCCGUUGGCCUGGGGGGGCUGAGGGACUGAGCCUCCCAGAGCAGGACCUCCCCCUGGAAGGGCCGCGCCGCAGCCCGUGGGAGGGCCUCGCCCCCGGCGCCCCCCAUCUCCACUCGCCGCCGUCCCGGCCUCCGCCGGAGGGAGGGGCCGAGCGCCCUCGGGGGGCCGUGGACCCCGGCGUUCUGAGCGUUCCGCGCCCCGCGCCGCCCGGCCCCCCCGCCGCCGAUGGCCGCCGACCCGCCGGGAGCUGCCGAGAAGGGAGAGAUGGCUCCCGGGACACGUGUGAGCCCUCGGCGUUGCUGACGCCCCCAAUGUCGUCGAGCAGCCGGGGGCCGGGGGCCGGAGCGCGCCGACGCCGAACCCGCUGCCGCCGCUGCCGGGCCUGUGUGCGAACUGAGUGCGGGGAUUGCCACUUCUGCCGAGACAUGAAGAAGUUCGGGGGGCCCGGGCGCAUGAAGCAGUCGUGCCUGCUCCGGCAGUGCACUGCCCCCGUGCUCCCACACACAGCUGUGUGCCUCUUGUGUGGGGAGGCUGGGAAGGAGGACACGGUGGAGGGAGAGGAAGAGAAAUUUGGUUUGAGCCUCAUGGAGUGUACAAUCUGCAACGAGAUCGUCCACCCCGGCUGCCUGAAGAUGGGGAAGGCUGAGGGUGUCAUCAAUGCAGAGAUCCCCAACUGCUGGGAGUGCCCUCGCUGCACCCAGGAAGGCCGCACCAGCAAGGAUUCAGGUGAGGGGCCUGGCCGCCGUAGGGCCGACAACGGCGAGGAGGGCGCCAGCUUGGGGAGCGGAUGGAAGCUGACAGAGGAGCCACCGCUUCCACCGCCCCCGCCCAGGCGCAAGGGCCCCCUGCCUGCCGGGCCCCCCCCGGAGGACGUGCCUGGGCCCCCCAAACGAAAGGAAAGGGAGGCAGGGAAUGAGCCUCCCACCCCAAGGAAAAAGGUGAAAGGAGGCCGAGAGAGGCACCUGAAGAAGGUGGGUGGAGACGCCUGCCUCCUCCGAGGAUCGGACCCAGGCGGCCCGGGCCUGCUGCCCCCCAGGGUUCUGAAUCCGAGCCAGGCUUUCUCAUCCUGCCACCCUGGGCUCCCUCCCGAGAACUGGGAGAAACCAAAGCCGCCUUUGGCCUCUGCAGAGGGCCCAGCGGUGCCGUCCCCGUCCCCGCAGAGGGAGAAGCUAGAGCGUUUCAAGCGGAUGUGCCAGCUGCUGGAACGGGUGCCUGACACCUCCUCUUCCUCCUCGGACUCAGACUCCGACUCCGACUCUUCGGGCACAUCGCUGAGUGAGGACGAAGCCCCCGGCGAGGCCCGGAAUGGGCGACGGCCAGCCCGGGGCAGCUCUGGCGAGAAGGAGAACCGUGGGGGGCGGCGGGCUGUGCGCCCUGGCAGUGGGGGGCCCCUACUCAGCUGGCCCCUGGGCCCAGCCCCACCACCCCGGCCUCCACAGCUGGAGCGGCACGUGGUGCGGCCCCCGCCUCGAAGCCCUGAGCCCGACACACUCCCCUUGGCUGCUGGAUCCGACCACCCCCUGCCCCGGGCCGCCUGGCUUCGCGUCUUCCAGCACCUCGGGCCGCGGGAGCUGUGUAUCUGCAUGCGAGUCUGCCGAACUUGGAGCCGCUGGUGCUAUGACAAGCGUCUGUGGCCUCGAAUGGACCUGAGCCGGCGGAAGUCACUGACCCCGCCCAUGCUCAGUGGUGUGGUUCGCCGCCAGCCCCGUGCCCUGGACCUCAGCUGGACAGGUGUCUCCAAGAAGCAGCUCAUGUGGCUUCUGAACCGACUACAAGGCCUGCAGGAGCUGGUGCUCUCUGGCUGCUCCUGGCUCUCUGUCUCUGCCCUGGGCUCAGCCCCACUGCCAGCCCUGCGGCUCCUGGACCUCCGCUGGAUCGAGGAUGUUAAAGACUCCCAGCUCCGGGAGUUGCUGCUGCCUCCACCAGACACCAAACCAGGGCAAACAGAGAGCCGUGGUCGGCUGCAGGGGGUGGCAGAACUGCGUCUGGCAGGUUUGGAGCUGACAGAUGCCUCCCUGCGUCUCCUGCUGCGUCACGCACCCCAGCUGAGCGCCCUGGACCUGAGCCACUGCGCCCACGUCGGGGACCCCAGUGUUCACCUCCUCACGGCCCCCACGUCCCCACUCCGCGAGACCCUGGUGCACCUCAAUCUUGCUGGUUGCCACCGCCUAACGGACCACUGCCUCCCGCUGUUCCGCCGCUGCCCUCGUCUACGCCGCCUAGACCUGCGCUCCUGCCGCCAGCUCUCACCCGAAGCUUGUGCCCGGCUGGCAGCUGCCGGGCCCCCUGGCCCCUUCCGCUGCCCUGAGGAGAAGCUGCUUCUCAAGGACAGCUAGUUGGGCGCCCCCCACCCUCCCCCGGACUCGACAGGAGCCUGGACCUCCGGCUUCAUUUCACCCCUGCUGGGAGGCCAGGUUCCCACCUCACCACCCUGGGAUUCCUGAGUGUCAGUGACUUGGGAUUCCCACCCAGGGACUCAAGCCAGCCACCCCCUUCUUUCCCCCCUGCACUGAUAUCUCUGGGGGUUUCUCCUUCCUAUGUCCUGCCCCUGCUACCUGCUUCAUUGUCCAUCCCCUGGGGGAGUGGGUCAGAGGUACUGGAGGGUGCUGAGCCGAAGGGACGGUGGGAGGGGGGUUAUGGUGCAAGUGUUGGGGGGGAGAAUGGGGAAAGGACACACACAGGAUAUGGGAGCCAGGGGCUGGGGGAGGUGGAAGGGGCGGGGGGCGGGGCAGACAGCAGACCACCAAGGGUUCAGGGAACAAAGACCAGUUACUUGGAGUGGGGGGUGGGGGUGGGGCCACAAAAGGAAAACCGGAGGAGCAAUUGGGGAUCCAGGUGUCAGAGGUAGGGGAACCAGGGGCAAGCUGGGGCUGAGCUGGAGGUGGGGAUGAGAGCAGGUGUGGGGACAGCAAUACCCCCUUGGGGGUCACCUCUCUGCUUCCCCCCUCCCCAGGCUUCAGUUCCUUCCCCCUGACCCUGACUCCUUGAACGUCACUGAAAACGGCAGCUAUUGCAAGGAGUGGGGGCCGCGGGCAGCCGCUCUUCAGCUCGCGGCCCAGGGGAGUGGCGAGGGGCGCCCCAACCCCCUGCCCGCCUCUCCGCACAAUACUUGAACAUUCAUCUGUACUGAAGUGUUACUUGAACCGGGGGAAUCUCGGACCUGGGGGAGCCGGGGUGUGAGGGGACUGGACCAGCUUGGACUGAGACCUGAGACCGGGCCGGUGGGCGCCCAUUUGGGACUGCGCCACCCCCAGGCUUGUUCUUGUUUUACUGUAUUGAGCGGCGGCACCCGCCGGACCCGCAUUAUGGCUGGGGGCGCCAGCCCAAGAAUGGGGACCAUGGGACUCCUCCAGCCUGGCUCUUCCCACUCUUUCAUCGUCAUGGAAACUUGUAUCCCAUUUGCCCAGGGAACUGCCACUCCUGGUUGCCAUGGAAAUAGCAGCCAACGGACACCUCCCGAUGCCAGUGCUAAGGCUGGAAAUGGCCCCCUCUUAGUUGCCAUGGGAACCUAGUAACAGACUCUGCUGGCCCUCCUUCCCUGCCCCUUCCUCGAGCGCGGGGUGGGGCUUCGGGACCCCGGGGAUGAGCCGGGCCAGGUCCCGCCCCUCCGCGCAGGCCUCCGGGGGGCCGGGGCUUACCAUGUAGGGGAGGGGAGAUCUAUCCACAUACCUCAGGUAACAGGGAGGUGCGCGGGUGGGGGGAGGGCUGGGCGGACCAAAGGCCGGAGGGGUGGGGCCUGGGGAUAGCGAGAGGCUUGAGAAUGGGGCCGCUUGGGGGAGGGAAGAGGCAGCCCGGCGAGGGGCAAGCGGGGGACCCAGCCGGGCUGGGCCCCUGGGCCCCGGGUCUGUACAAUACGGUUUGCUAUAAAACUCAAAAUCUUCCAGCCGGG